UCUGAUUUUUCAGGCAGCGCUGUUCAUAAGAUGAUUGUGGACAGGCAGUAUAUGGGCGUGUCUAAGCGGAAGUGCAUCGUGUGGGGUGUCGCCUUCUUGUCCGAUGGCACUAUCAUAAGUGUGGACUCUGCUGGGAAGGUGCAGUUCUGGGACUCAGCCACUGGGACGCUUGUGAAGAGCCAUCUCAUCGCUAAUGCUGACGUGCAGUCCAUUGCUGUAGCUGACCAAGAAGACAGUUUCGUGGUGGGCACAGCCGAGGGAACAGUCUUCCAUUUUCAGCUGGUCCCUGUGACAUCUAACAGCAGUGAGAAGCAGUGGGUGCGGACAAAACCGUUCCAGCAUCACACUCAUGACGUGCGCACUGUGGCCCACAGCCCAACAGCGCUGAUAUCUGGAGGCACUGACACCCACUUAGUCUUUCGUCCUCUCAUGGAGAAGGUGGAAGUAAAGAAUUACGAUGCCGCUCUCCGAAAAAUCACCUUUCCCCACCGAUGUCUCAUCUCCUGUUCUAAAAAGAGGCAGCUUCUCCUCUUCCAGUUUGCUCAUCACUUAGAACUUUGGCGACUGGGAUCCACAGUUGCAACAGGCAAGAAUGGGGAUACUCUUCCACUCUCUAAAAAUGCAGAUCAUUUACUGCACCUAAAGACAAAGGGUCCUGAGAACAUUAUCUGUAGCUGUAUCUCCCCAUGUGGAAGUUGGAUAGCCUAUUCUACAGUUUCUCGGUUUUUUCUCUAUCGGCUGAAUUAUGAACAUGACAACAUAAGCCUCAAAAGGGUUUCCAAAAUGCCAGCAUUCCUUCGCUCUGCCCUUCAGAUUUUGUUUUCUGAAGAUUCAACAAAGCUCUUUGUAGCAUCAAAUCAAGGAGCUCUGCAUAUUGUUCAGCUGUCAGGAGGAAGCUUCAAGCACCUGCAUGCUUUCCAGCCUCAGUCAGGAACAGUGGAGGCCAUGUGUCUUUUGGCAGUCAGUCCAGAUGGGAAUUGGCUAGCUGCAUCAGGUACCAGUGCUGGAGUCCAUGUCUACAACGUAAAACAGCUAAAGCUUCACUGCACGGUGCCUGCUUACAAUUUCCCAGUGACUGCUAUGGCUAUUGCCCCCAAUACCAACAACCUUGUCAUCGCUCAUUCGGACCAGCAGGUAUUUGAGUACAGCAUCCCAGACAAACAGUAUACAGAUUGGAGCCGGACUGUCCAGAAGCAGGGCUUUCACCACCUUUGGCUCCAAAGGGAUACUCCUAUCACACACAUCAGUUUUCAUCCCAAGAGACCGAUGCACAUCCUUCUCCAUGAUGCCUACAUGUUCUGCAUCAUUGACAAGUCAUUGCCCCUUCCAAAUGACAAAACCUUACUCUACAAUCCAUUUCCUCCCACGAAUGAAUCAGAUGUCAUCCGGAGGCGCACAGCUCAUGCUUUUAAAAUUUCUAAGAUAUAUAAGCCUCUACUCUUCAUGGAUCUUUUGGAUGAAAGAACACUCGUGGCAGUAGAACGGCCUCUGGAUGACAUCAUUGCUCAGCUCCCACCACCCAUUAAAAAGAAGAAAUUUGGAACCUAAAACAGGGCACUGUCUGUGUCCUUCCUUGAACUGUCUACCCUGUUGCUUUUCACAAAUCAUGGUAAUAAAACAAGUUAUUCUUGA